AUACCAGAAUUGCUGUUAACAAAUAAAAUACUGGCCAGAUGUGUUGGUUCACGCCUGUAAUCCUAGCACUUCGGGAGGCUGAGGCGGGAGGAUUACUUGAGCCUAGGAGUUUGAGACCAGCCUGGGCAACAUAGCAAGAUCCCAUCUCUACAAAAAAGUGAAAAAGUUAGCUGAACAAGGCGGCAUGCACAUGCUACUCCAGACGCUGAAGUGGGAAGAUCACUUAAGUCCGAGAGAUCGAGGCUUCAGUGAGAUAUGGCUGAGACACUGCUCUCAGCCUGGAUGACAGAGAUUGGAGACACAAAAUCAGAAAUUAAGAUUCUAAGCAUAGGCGGAGGUGCAGGUGAAAUUGAUCUUCAAAUUCUCUCCAAAGUUCAGGCUCAAUACCCAGGAGUUUGUAUCAACAAUGAAGUUGUUGAGCCAAGUGCUGAACAAAUUGCCAAAUACAAAGAGCUUGUAGCCAAGACAUCGAACCUCGAGAACGUAAAGUUUGCUUGGCAUAAGGAGACAUCAUCUGAAUACCAAAGUAGAAUGUUGGAGAAAAAGGAGCUUCAAAAGUGGGACUUUAUUCAUAUGAUUCAAAUGCUGUAUUAUGUAAAAGACAUCCCAGCUACCCUGAAAUUCUUCCAUAGUCUCUUAGGUACCAAUGCUAAGAUGCUCAUUAUUGUUGUGUCAGGAAGCAGUGGCUGGGACAAGCUGUGGAAAAAGUACGGAUCACGCUUUCCCCAGGAUGACCUCUGCCAGUAUAUCACAUCAGAUGACCUCACUCAGAUGCUGGACAACCUAGGGCUUAAGUAUGAGUGCUAUGACCUUUUGUCCACCAUGGAUAUAUCUGACUGCUUUAUUGAUGGUAAUGAAAAUGGAGACCUGCUUUGGGAUUUUUUGACUGAAACCUGCAACUUUAAUGCCACAGCACCACCUGAUCUCAGAGCAGAGCUUGGGAAAGAUCUACAAGAGCCUGAAUUUAGUGCUAAGAAAGAGGGGAAGGUUCUUUUUAAUAAUACUCUGAGUUUCAUAGUGAUUGAGGCAUAACUAUCAAUCACAAAAGUAUAUUCAAAAAUUAUAUUUUGAACAACUCGAAUCACUCAUUUAUUUCCAUAUUAAAAUCACAAACUCAUCCAUUAAUGUAGAUAAAGCACUGUUUGGAUAUGAGAUGUAGCAAAUUCCAAUACAUUAUUGGACUUCCAUUUGGAAUCAUAUGGGAUACUGCUGGUCUUAUCCUGUCCCUCCUCCAGGUAGAGAGACCACAAGCAGGCUCAACAUAACAUAAGCUAGAAAAAUUAGAUGACUGAAUUUCUAUGGCAUAUUGAUAAUAAAAUUCAUUCCAUUUGCUGAUUGUCUGAAAUUUUCUAGAAUACUAAUAAAAUACAUACUAUAGAUUCUUUAUUAGUGAAGUAUGCACUAAUCAAUACUUUGAACACAAAGCCUGUGUUACUGAUUUGGCCGUUUUGUGAAGAAACAUUUAUCUUUGUACGUUCUUCUAUUGUGCUUUCUAUCUAAUUUUUAUUAAUUUGUAAGAGUAAGCACCUUUAGAAUAUUAAAAAUUAAUUCUUUAUCACAUGUUGUCAUUUCUUCCCAUUGUGUUUUCUCUUGUAAUUUUAUCUGUGAAUUAAUAGCUUUUUGUUUGUCUUUUUGAUAUACUGAAGUUUUCUAUUAUAUUCAGCCAGAUUUUUUUUUAAGUCUCGGCUUCUGAUACAUUUUAAAAGACCUUCUAAAACCAAGGUUUUAGAAUACUAACAUUUUAUCAAAAUAAUAUUAUAGUUUUGCUUUUUUUAAAAAAUGAAAUCUUUACUAUGUUUGAAAUUUAGAUAAGUAUAAACAGUGAGAACAAACUGUUUCCCCUCAAAAUAAUAGCCAGAUGUAUAAACAAAAUUUAUUGAAGAACAAAGAAACACAAAACUAAACCUGUUCUAGCUUAAAAUGCAGCUUUUACCAGAUUUCUAGGAAUUGGGUAAAUGCAAGGUUCUAGAAAACCUUCAAUGCAUUUUGAUACUUUAUAGUUUCUUAUGUCACUCUCAAGAACUCCUAUAAGACCAAGAGUCAUCUUUGGACUGUAGGAUUUCAGGGGGGUUUUGAAAACAAAUUUGAUGUUUCUUAUUUUUAAUAAUAACGCUCUGUUAUUUUUGACAUAAACAGUACAUUUAAUAAUUAAUAAAUAAAUAUUUUAAGUAUGUAAAUAAUUAGUACUCCCUGUCACAAACAAAACAAAAGUAAGGUUUUACUAAACAGCUCAUGAGCCCUCAUUCUGCCAGUGAGGAAGCCUUCAACCCCGUGUGAUACUCACUCUUUCAUGCAAUAGGGCUUCCAUGUAAUGUUGCCGUAUAAUCACUUUAAAAAGUUAAACGACCCAUCUCAAUCACCUAGUUUAUCCCCAGGGAAUACACUGGCAUAGAGAGCCUAUUUACACUAAUAAACUACCAAGCUUUGUUGUUCAUAAUAAGUAAAAUGGACUUGCAUUGCUCUCUUUUUUGGACAACUUCAUCAAUGCUUUUUGAAUUAUAUGUUUCAACAAAUGAAACGACAGUUAUCCAAUCAGAUUCCUGAAAAUGAACACUGAACCGUUAAUCAUACUGAUAUGUACUACUGACAAAGGAAAUCUGUGAGGCACACAUGAUUGAUGGGUAUGGGGCCAUGAAGACCUUGAAGAGCUUCACCAGAAGUAUGGAAAUCAAGACUUUACAGAGUCUUUUGUAUAAAGCACACGUGCAAAAACAAACAAAAUUAGAACUAACAAUGCUAUUGAAAGAUACAAAAGAAUUGCAGUCCAUAGAUUGGUGUUUGUAAAUAUGGCCUUUUUCUCGUCCUUAUUAAACCCUUAGUAUACAAGGAUAAAUAAAUUCUCACCUGCUUAAUUUUAGUGCAAUUGAAACACAUAAGCCUUUUUAAAGAGAGAAAUUCCCAUGAAAACCUACUAGUCAGCAAUGGGAAGUUGUAUAAAUUCAAGGGAUAAACCUAUCCCUGUUUUCUUCCUGCACUGUAUGAUAAUACCAAAAUUUGGGACAGUCACAUACUAACUUUUCAGAUUUGUUCUUGUGUUUCAGAAAAAAGUGCUCAGCAUGAAUUUGGAAUGUUGUUUUAUGUAUUGUUGUGGAUCUCUCAGUGUUUAACAUGGUGCCUUGCAUAUGGUAAAUGCUAAGUAAAGCGGGAUCAAUGAAUUAUUUCCUUCUCAAACAUUUAUCUUAUACCUUGUGUGUUCAUAUUAUUAUUAUAAACAGAGCUCAAGAAACCCAAUAAAGUUAUGUGUUGCCAGUGUAAACCUUAACUUA